UGAGGCCCUGCCUCACACUGGCCUCUCUCACGCUGAGGGAGGUCAGCGUGAGGCCCUGCCUCACACUGGCCUCUCUCACGCUGAGAGAAGUCCUCCCUCACGCUGGCCUGUUGAGGCCCAGUUCAUGCCUCUGUUGGCUUCUCCAGGCCCAGCCCCUGCCUGUUGGCGGCCUCUACCUCAACAGUGGGCCCUCCACGCCCACCUCUUGCCUCGCCGUGGCCUCCUCGGGCCAGGCUCCCGCCUUGGGGCGGCCCCCGCAGGCCCAGCUCCUGCCUCACGGCCCUCCAGAGGCCAAGCUCAUGCGUCAGGGCGGCCUCUCCCGGCCUGGCGUUUGCUCCUUUGCAUGGGCUCCAAAUCCUGUACUUCCUCCAGUCGUUCUCUCCAGGCCCAGCUCUUCCUCCCAGCAGCCUCUGCAGGACCAGACUGUCGUCAAGUAGGCCUGUCCAGGGACAGCUCCUGCCUCCCGGCAGACUCUGCAGGCCCAAGUCGUCCUCAAGUCAGCCUCCCCAGGCCCAACUCCGGCCUCUCGGCGGCCUCUCCAGGUGCAAAAGUUCCUCGAGUCCGUCUCUCCAGGUCCAGCUCCUCCUGUCUCCCAGUGGCCUCUUUCAGCCCAGCCCAGCUCAUGCCUCCCGGCGGCCUUCCCAGGCCCCGCUUCUGACUUUCCGCGGCCUCUGCAGGCCCCGAACUUGACCUCCAGUCGGCCUCUGCAGGCCUGGCCUCCUGCCUCCCGAAAGCUUGCACAGGCCCAGCCUGUGCCUCACAGCGGACCCUCCACGCCCAGCUCGCUCUCGCCUGCGGCCUCCCGAGUCCAAAGCUCCGGCCUCUCCGCCGCUUCGGCAGGCCCAGCUCCCGCCUGCCAGUGGCCUCCUCAGGCCCAUGGGGCUCAUUCCUCACAACGGCCUUUCCCGGCCCAGUUUUUCCCUUCCGGCGGCCUCUCCGGGCCCAGAAGCUCCUCAAGUCGGCCUCUCCAGACCCACUUGCAGCCUCCCGGCGUCCUCUCCGGGCCCAGCUCUUCCUCCCGGCUGCAUCUGCAGGCCCGGCUCCUGCCUCCCAACAACCUCUUUGGACUCAGUGCCUGCCCAGCUCCUGGUGGCCUUGGUCGGCCCACAGCUUCCUCAAGCCAAGCUCCCCAGGCCCAGCUCAGGCCUCACGGUGGCCUCUCCAGGCUCAGCUCCUGCCCUCCGACGGCGUCUCCAGGCCCCAAACGGCCUCCGGUCGGUGGGCUUCUCCAGGCCCAGCUUGGGCCUCCCGGCGGCCU